AGUCAUUGGAGGUGCUUUCUGCUGAGUGAGCGCCCUGGGUGGUGUGCAUAAAUGAGCUGCCACUUCCCAGGGAGCCCUCCGUGGGCUCUUGCUGGUCAGCCCGGGGCCUCAGCCCCCGACUGGUCCACACCUGACCCAUUCGCCGCCUUCCUGCUCUCCCAGGUGCAAGCCCUGGAACAGCGCAACCAGCUGCUGGAGACACGCUGGAGCUUCCUGCAGGGCCAGGACUCAGCCAUCUUCGACCUCGGGCAUCUCUAUGAGGAAUAUCAGGGCCGGCUGCAGGAGGAACUGCGCAAAGUGAGCCAGGAGCGGGGGCAGCUGGAGGCCAACCUGCUGCAGGUGCUGGAGAAGGUUGAGGAGUUUCGAAUCAGGUAUGAGGAUGAGAUCUCCAAGCGCACAGACAUGGAGUUCACCUUUGUUCAGCUGAAGAAGGUAGCCUGCCCAGCCUGCCCCAGGGGCUCCUUCCUCAUGGGCCCUGGGCCCUCUUUCCCUCCAGAUAUCCUACUCUCCUUUAUGCCCAAUCAAAGCCCUCAGAGGCUUAAGUCCCAGGACCAACAGACAGACAGGGAGAUACCCCCAUCCCCAUCCAGCUCCUUUUUCGAGGCUCUGAGCCAGAUCUCCUCUGGAAUCACCCCCACUCUCACCCAGGAGGCAGCCCCCCAGCCCACUCCUGCCCUGGGACCCUCCAUUCCCUCUCCCACCACUCACCACUGCUGCCAACCCCAGGACCUGGAUGCAGAGUGUCUUCAUCGGACUGAACUGGAAACCAAGUUAAAAAGCCUGGAGAGCUUCGUGGAGUUGAUGAAAACCAUCUAUGAGCAGGAGCUGAAGGACCUGGCAGCACAGGUGAAGGAUGUGUCGGUGACCGUCGGCAUGGACAGCCGCUGCCACAUCGACCUGAGCGGCAUCGUGGAGGAGGUGAAGGCCCAGUAUGACGCCGUCGCGGCUCGCAGCCUGGAGGAGGCCGAGGCAUACUCUCGGAGCCAGCUGGAGGAGCAGGCCGCCCGCUCGGCCGAGUAUGGGAGCAGCCUCCAGAGCAGCCGCAGCGAGAUCGCGGAUCUCAAUGUGCGCAUCCAGAAGCUGCGGUCCCAGAUCCUCUCUGUCAAGAGCCAUUGCCUGAAACUGGAGGAGAACAUCAAGACAGCUGAGGAGCAGGGUGAGCUGGCCUUCCAGGAUGCCAAGACCAAGCUGGCCCAGCUGGAGGCCGCCCUGCAGCAGGCCAAGCAGGACAUGGCGCGGCAGCUGCGCAAGUACCAGGAGCUGAUGAACGUCAAGCUGGCCCUGGACAUCGAGAUCGCCACCUACAGGAAGCUGGUGGAGGGCGAGGAGGGCAGGAUGGACUCGCCCUCAGCCACUGUGGUCAGCGCUGUGCAGUCCAGGUGCAAAACCGCUGCCUCCAGAUCAGGCCUCUCCAAGGCCCCCUCCCGAAAGAAGAAGGGCAGCAAAGGCCCCGUGAUCAAAAUCACCGAAAUGUCAGAGAAGUACUUCUCGCAGGAGUCGGAGGUCUCAGAGUAAGGCGGCUGGACCCCAGGAACCCCAGGGCACUCCACUGCAGCAGGAGGGACUUAAGCUAGACUCAAGAAAGCAGCUUGGAGCCUCUAGGUUGAGAAGAGAGGCAAAACCUGAUAUUGAACUGAGAGAGGGGUUCAAAACUGACUGUGUUUUGUGGGCUGCCAGGGUGGGAGAGGAGCAUCACCAGCUCCUCAGAGCCACUCCGCUCCAUAUCAGUAUCUCACAGUCCCAUCCUUCCAACCUUCUGGCCAGAGGUUUUCCUGAUGGGUGAGUCGGAAUUAGGGGUCAGUUUUGUCUCCACCUCCUCGCUCCUCUGAGGCUCCUCCUCCAGCAUCAGGCUCUGCCAAGGCCCCUCUGACUCUUGCCCAAUCCUUGACCUUGACUCCUAUCUCAAGCCUUGCCUUGUCUCUGCCUCGGAACUGGGACUGGGACUGGCUCAUCCACCUAUGUGCGGGAGCCGAGGAGGACGGCGUGGGCCCUGUCCUGUAUCUGGAAUUCCUGGGAAGGCUGGCUGCUGAAGACCCUCUUGGCUUUCCCGUGCUCUUUGGGCUCCCCAGAGACCUGACAGUAUUAGGGAGUGAAGGGAGGAGGGGCCCUGGCUAUUUGGGACCUAAGCCUAGGCCCCAGAGAUCAGCCCGAACACCCGCAUCCCUUCCUCCUCCCAUGGGUCCCUCCCAGUAGGCAGUAGUCAGAACUGGAUGGGCUGCCCCCAGCCAGCUCCCAGCAGCUUCUCCGGAAGCUGCUCUUGCCAUAAUCAACUCCCUGGGAGUGGAAGCCAGAUGGCAGCUUGAGAUUGGGCAGGAGCAUUCGAUCUUCCUUUCACCUCCCUGCCAUGCUGGGGUCCUACCCAGCCUGGAUCUGAGCUCUGUGCCCCCAGCCGGGUUGUUCCCAGCCUGAGCACCGGGCUUUGGUGCACCAGGCCUUGGAGACCCCUGGUCCCACCCCUGCCGUGAAGCCCCAGGCCCACUUCCCAAGAAUCUCACUUCUCAGGGCCUCUGUUCUCCUCUCCACUGGGCCAAAUAGCCUGGCCCUCCCCUCCUUGGCAUUCAUGGGGGAGCCCAGGAACCCCCCACACCUAUGGGGUUAGAGCUCCUCCUUUCUUCUCACUCCUUCCCCUUCCUCCCUCCAUGCCCACUCCCCCUGCCUCCAGCAGGCCAGGAAGAAGGCACAGUCCAGGCAAGUCUGGGAGCUUCCAAGCCCUUGAGGUCCAGCUGUGGGGCCCAAAUGACAGCCUUACAAGGGUUCUACCAGAGAGGAAAAUUCCACAUCCCACCAGAAGACAGGGGUGUUGGCAGGCAUACUCCUAUCUCCUCCUCUUGGCUCUCAAUGCUGAGGCUUGCAGAGGCAUCCCAGCGGCACCAGCCUCCCACUGCACAGCUUCCUUCCCUCCUUCACUCUCCUCUCCCCUCCCUGCCCCUUGCCUCACCUCCUCUUCUAGACUGCAUUAGAUUCAUUCAUCUCAUUUGCCAGGACAUGUUGGCCAGAGGUCUGGGCCCAUCCCAGGCCUCAAGGCCCUCCAGGCCUGUGGGGAGCACUGGAGGGUUACUGACUCUCUGGCCAUGGGAACUCAGAGAUUCUCAUCCCCAAAGUCCCAAAAGAGGGUGCUGAUUGGUGCUUUUCCUCAGGCUCUUCAUUGGUUUCCAAGGGAGCAAAUCCUCAGUGGGGAUACAAGACAUAUAAAGUAUAUAUUAUUUUUUCAUAACUUAUGUGGCUUUUAACUUAUUGCUUCCCUUCCUGUUUCUGCAUGAUCAGUCUGUAUGUACUAUCUGGAAAGAUAACACAUACUCCAGCCACCUCACCUGAUUGGCUAUCUUGGGGCCAUGUCCCCUUCUUGCUGCCACAGGAUGAAUAAAGUGUUGAGAUUUGUCUAUGGAGAAAGCUGUGUGUCUGUUUUUAUCUCCCCUCUCAGGACCAGUCAGCCACUGGUCAAUCAGGCUGAUCAUGGAACAUUAGGAAUUCUCCAAUUAAGGGAGAAAAAGUCCAGGGACUUAGUUAUAUCUUCAGACCAGUGCAGCUGGUACACACAAAGUUCUCCUGUCUCACCAUCUGAUAUGGUUUGGAUGCUCGUCCCCUCCAAAUCUCAUGUUGAAAUGUAAUUCCCAGUGUUGGAAGUGGAGCCUGGUGGGAAGUAUUUGGAUCAUGAGAGAGGAUCCUUCAUGAAUGGCUCAGCACCAUCUCCUUGGUGAUGAGUGAGUUCUCACUCAAUUCACAUAGAUAUGGUUGUUUAAAAGAGUCUGAGACCUCUCCCCUCUUUCUCGCCAUGUGAUAUGCCUGCUCCCCCUUCACCUUCCGCCUUUACUGUAAGCUUCCUGAGGCCCUCACCAGAAGCUGAGCAAAUGUUGGUGCCAUGCCAGUACAGCCUGCAGAAUUGUGAGCCAAAAUAAAUGUCUUUUCUUUAUAAAUUA